GGUUUUGCUCCGCUUUAGCAGCGGCGAAGGGAGGACCCCCGGGAGCCGGUCCCCGGCGUCCGGUCGCCCAGCCCUUUUCAGGCUUGGGCCCGCAUGGAGGGGACCGUGGAGUCCCAGACGCCUGACCUGCGGGAUGUGGAGGGUAAGGUGGGCAGGAAGACCCCUGAAGGGCUGCUCCGCGGGCUGCGAGGCGAGUGUGAGCUGGGAACCUCUGGCGCCCUGCUGCUCCCAGGGGCGUCUAGCACCGGCCACGACUUGGGGGACAAGAUCAUGGCGCUGAAGAUGGAGCUGGCUUACCUGCGAGCCAUCGAUGUGAAGAUCCUGCAGCAGCUGGUGACCUUGAAUGAGGGCAUCGAGGCAGUGCGCUGGCUGUUGGAGGAGCGGGGGACGUUGACCAGUCAUUGCAGCAGCCUCACCAGCAGUCAAUAUAGCCUGACAGGCGGGAGCCCAGGCCGCUCAAGGCGAGGCAGCUGGGACAGCCUGCCAGACACCAGCACCACCGACCGGCUGGACAGUGUCUCUAUUGGCAGCUUCCUGGACACAGUGGCCCCCAGCGAGCUGGAUGAACAGGGCCCACCUGGGGCUCCACGUUCCGAGAUGGACUGGGCAAAAGUUAUAGCUGGUGGAGAGAGGGCCAGGACUGAGGUGGAUGUGGCAGCCACCAGGCUAGGGAGCUUGAGAGCUGUGUGGAAGCCCCCAGGGGAGAGGCUUCAAGGUGGACCACCUGAGUCACCAGAGGAUGAGAGUGCCAAGCUGGGCUUCGAGGCCCACUGGUUCUGGGAGCAGUGCCAGGAUGAUGUGACCUUCUUGUAACAACUAUUCCACCCUUUUGUAAUCCUGUGGCUCUUUUAUCCAUUAGAUGUGGUCUCCCCCAAAAUUGAUUCUCCCUCAGUCUGAGACUAGGAAGAGGCUGCACUGAAAUCAGUUACCAUGGAAACCUGGCUCAUCAUUUCUCUAGUCCCUAGGGAGUCUCUGCCUUUAUCCCUCAAUUAUUGGGUCCCUAGAGCUAGCUUGCUCUUUCUUUCUUUCUUUCUUUUUUUGAGACAGGGUCUUAUGCUGUUACCCAAGAUAGAGAGCAGUGGCAUGAUCACAGCUCACUGCAGCCUUGACCUCCUGGGCUCAAGCGAUCCUCCUAUUUCAGCCUCCCCCAUAGUUAGGACCACAGGCAUGCACCACCAUGCCCAGCUAAUUGUUUAUUUAUUUAUUUUUUUUUUGUAGAGAUAGGGUUUCCCUGUGUUGCCCAGGCUGGUCUCAAACUCCUGGGCUCAAGGGAUCCUCCCGCCUCAGCCUCCCAAAGUGCUGGGAUUAUGCCCAGCCCCUAGAGAUACUUCUAUAGAGAUAUUGACUCUAAAGGAUUGACCUAUGGCUUUUGGUAUUUAGUAUCUCUCACUACUCCCCCCAGCUAAGUAAGGAUUUAAGGAAUUUAGGACUCCCUGGAGUUAACAGAUGAAGAGAUGGGGGCAUAAUUACUUCACCCAAAGUCUAGAAGCCUUGGCCUCUCUCUUGGCCAAGAUGGAGGAUUGAGGAGGGACAUGGACCUUCAGGACUAACCCUCUAUGGAUUGGCCCUCCCAGAAGCGUUUGGGCUGGUAGACCCACCCCUUCCUACCUGCUGAGUGAUGUCAUUUCCUGCCAGGAUGGGUAGCCCUUUGUACGGGUCCUUGGAUGGUAGUAGGUCAUAUAGGGGCAUCUGAGCCCCUGCUGCUAAGUGAGAUCACAUUAUUUAUCGUCCAUACCAUUACUUCUUGUGAACAGUAACAUGUCACUCCUCCUGGCAGGAAAGUUUCUCAUUGUCAGAUGUUUGUGCUUCUUUUCAGGUCUUACUUUUUAAAUAGAGUGUUCUCAUUUUA